AGUCGCUGAGUGCCUGAGCCGGGAAGCAGUUGCUGUGGUACCUGCUGCUGCCCGAGCGGACGUAGAGCAUCGGACGCGGGCGCCGUGGCGCUGGGCAGGAGGGCGAAGCCAUGACGUCAGUCAGAGAAAAUAUUCUCUUUGGAAUGGGAAAUCCUCUGCUUGACAUCUCUGCUGUAGUGGACAAAGAUUUCCUUGAUAAGUAUUCUCUGAAACCAAAUGACCAAAUCUUGGCUGAAGACAAACACAAGGAACUGUUUGAUGAACUUGUGAAAAAAUUCAAAGUCGAAUAUCAUGCUGGUGGCUCUACCCAGAAUUCAAUUAAAGUGGCUCAGUGGAUGAUUCAACAGCCACACAAAGCAGCAACAUUUUUUGGAUGCAUUGGGAUAGAUAAAUUUGGGGAGAUCCUGAAGAGAAAAGCUGCUGAAGCCCAUGUGGAUGCUCAUUACUACGAGCAGAAUGAGCAGCCAACAGGAACUUGUGCUGCAUGCAUCACUGGUGACAACAGGUCCCUCAUAGCUAAUCUUGCUGCUGCCAAUUGUUAUAAAAAGGAAAAACAUCUUGAUCUGGAGAAAAACUGGAUGUUGGUAGAAAAAGCAAGAGUUUGUUAUAUAGCAGGCUUUUUUCUUACAGUUUCCCCAGAGUCAGUAUUAAAGGUGGCUCACCAUGCUUCUGAAAACAACAGGAUUUUCACUUUGAAUCUAUCUGCACCGUUUAUUAGCCAGUUCUACAAGGAAUCAUUGAUGAAAGUUAUGCCUUAUGUUGAUAUACUUUUUGGAAAUGAGACAACUUACCACAUCUGAGAGAAACCUGACAUGUGGGCAUACUUCAGCGAUCCUUAAUAGAGUGGCCCUCUUGCUUCCAAGUGUCUUGAAGCUGCCAGCCAGAUCUCUAACAUACGUCAGUACAGGAAAAGGCAAGAGAAGGAUUGUGAAAGCUGUCAUCUAUAGGUUUCUUCGACUUCAUUGUGGCCUUUGGAUGAGAAGGGCUGGUUAUAAGAAAAAAUUAUGGAAAAAGGCACCUGCAAGAAAAAAGCGAUUGAGGGAAUUUGUAUUCGGCAAUAAAACCCAGAGUAAACUCUUAAGAUAAAAUGACGACGUCCUUCUGGAAGAGGUGAAACUGGUAUGUCCAUGAUCCUUAUCAGAAGUGUCAUGAUCGAACAAACCUGAAAGUAUAGAUCAGAAGUUUCACUUGUUUCUCAGUUAUUGAAUAUGUAUCUUUGUGUACAUAUCUGCAAAAAUGGAUAAGUAAAAAUCUCGAUGUAAAUUGUAUCAAUGAAUAUGUAAACAUACAGUGACAACACUGAACUUAUAAAAGUUUUAAAACUUAAAAAAAAAGCUCAAAUUUGUAAAAGACAUGUAAAAAGAAGGUGGAAAAUGUAUUUAGAAUCAGGGAAUGAUGCUAAAAGUUUGGUAGAGACAAAAGAGAAAAGAAAGUCCCAAAAGUGGUUUAAGUUUGCAGCAGAUGCUGAUGAUAUCAAAACAAUCUUCACUUAAAAAAAAAAAAAAGACUCCAAAGUACAAGCAACAAAUGGAAAAAAUAGAUAAAUUAGACAUCAUCAAAAUUAACAAUUUUUGGGCAUCGAAGGACACUAACAAGAAUGUGAAAAGACAACUAGUGGAAUGGGAGUUAAUAUUUGCAAAUCAUAUAUCUGAUAAAGGAUUCAUAUUCAGAAUAUUUAACACAGUAACAACUCAACAAUAAGCAAACUAACAACAUAAUUCAAUAAUGAUCAAAGGAAUUUAAUAAACAUUUAUUCGAAGAAGAUAUACAGAUGGCCAGUAAACACAUGAAAAGAUGCUCAACAUAACCAUUCAAGAAGUGCAAAUCAAAACCAAAAUUAGAUACCACUUCACACCCAUCAGAAUGACAAUUGUUUUAAAAAAUGGAAAUUAACAAGUAUUGGUGAAGAUGUGGAGAAAUUGGAAACACUUGUGUAUUGCUGGUGGGAAUGUAAAAUGGGAAUGUAGAAGACAAUUUGGUGGUUCCUCAAAAUGUUAAACAUAGAAUUAUUACCAUAUGAUCUAGCAGUUCUACUUCUAGGUAUAUUACCCAAAAUAACUGAAAGCAGGGACUCAGAUAAUUGUACACCAAUGUCCAUAGCAGCAUUAUUCACAAUAGCUAAGAUAGAAGCAAAUCAAAUAUUCAUCAACAGAUGAAUAAACAAAAUUUCAUGUAUAUAUACAAUGGAGUAUUAUUUAGCCUUAAAUAAAAUUUUGAUACAUGCUACAACAUGAAUGAAUUUUGGAAAUACUAUGUUAAGUAAAAUAAGCCAGACACAUCAGACAAUUAUUGGAUUUUCUAAGAAGAAUUCCACUUACAAGAAGUAUCUAGAAUAGGCAAAUUCAUAGAGACACAUAGUAGGAUAGUGAUUACCUGGGAGUGGGGUGGGGAGGAAUGAGGCAUUAUUGUGUAAUAAGUACAGAGCUUCUGUUUGGGAUGAUGAAAAAGUUCUGGAAAUGGAUAGUGGUGAUAGUUGCGCCACACUGUGAAUGUAUUUAGUGCCAAUGAAUUGCAUACUUAAAAUGGAAAAUUUUAUCAUAUGUAUAGUUUACCACAAUUUUUUUGAAAAAGUUUUAUUCUACAAAUCAGUAAACUUAAAAGUUGGAUCACAGCUUAGCAUAGAUUAUUAAAGGAAUUAUUUUUCCCCACCUAGAAGAGGAAGUGGUAAAACUGUAAGCUGCUACGUGGCUGUAAGUCAUGGGGCAAGAAAAUCUUUUCUCUUUUGGUAUGAUUAUUGUUCAUUUGAAUUCGCUUCAAGAGGUAUUUAUAUAGUACCUAAGUACCUAUUAUGGCAGACCAAUAAGCAGUGGAUACAUAGUAUAUUUUAGAACAUCUGUCAUUACGUGGACUAUAGAAUAAUAAAGAUUGGCUAUAAGACAAUUAGAGGUAUUUGGUAUUUUAUUGAAGCAGUCUCAAAAGGUCUGUUGAUAAAUAAAUUGAUUUCUAGGGGUACGCCUCAGUGUUUACCCUGCCUUUGCUUAAGUAAACAGUGAUUUAGAUAAAGCUAUAUUUGCAUAUAAUUCAAAUGCAAAUAAUACAACACCUUAAUACAUACUAGGUAAGUUGAAGGUCAAAAUCAGAUUUUUUUAAAUGUUAGUAGACUCUAAAUAUCAGUUGAGUGAUGAAAUUUAAUAGGGAUAAUAAAAAUUAUAUCGUAUUUGAUUAUAAAAAGCAAGUAGAGUAAAAUGCUUUAUCCCUUUAAUCUCAUCAUCCAUUGUUUUUCUCCUUGAAUACUAUAGUGAUAAUGUUAUCUUCAGUUUUCCAGGAAAAAAGAGACAUUUUACUUCUAAAAUGUGACGAAGGAUAAAAUAUAGUUAUCAGAGAAUAUACGUAGGAUUCUUUAAUAUUUCCCCCCUCAAAAAAAUAAAGUAUACUGUGUUUAGUAUAAAUUUUUAAAAUGUCAAAACUCAGCUAAAAUCAAACACACUUGGCCCUUAUUUUCUACAUGUCACCUUCCUCUUGUCAGAGGAUUGUACAGUAGUAAUGAUGAUUUAAAACUUCUGAUAGCCUCAAUAUUUAAAAAAAAUAAUACCUUGUCCACAAAGAUUAUUUCUUCACAGGCAAUGAUCAAUGAUCCCUGUGAGACAAGAAAUAAAUAAGAUAAACCUGAUGAUUACCCCAGCUAACUCCUUGGAGAUAAUUUCCAGGCAACAGAAGAAAGGUAACUAAGGCCAAGCACAGUGGCUCACGCCUGUAAUACCAGCACUUUGGGAGGCUGAAGCGAGUGGAUCCUUUGAGGUCAGGAGUUCAAGACCAGCCUGGCCAACAUGGUGAAACCCCCUCUCUACUAAAAAUACAAAAAAGCCUGGCAGGGUGGUUGUGCGCCUGUAAUCCCAGCUACUCGGGUGGCUGAGGCAUGAGAAUUACUUGAACCUGGGAAGCAGAGGUUGCAGCGAGCCAAAAUUGCACCACUGCACUCCAGCCAGUGUGAUUGAGACUCUGUCUCAAAAAGAAAAAAGAAGGGUAUCUCAAGUAGACCCUUGCAGUCUCUUUUAAUGAGGAGUUGGAGCCGGAAGUUCAAGGAGUCUAAGACAGCUAGUGUUUGUAAGUUAAAAGUACCAGAGAAGAAAUAGCUGAAUAGAGGGAGAACACAGGACAUUUGCAGAAUCCCAACAAGUCUUCAGCUGAGUAUGAAUCAGUGCAUUUUUGUGAAGAAAUUAAGGAAGACCACAAAAAGAACCACCUAAAAAGAUUGUAGAAGACAAUCCUCAGUGCACACAUGAGGACCUAUAACCAUUCCUAUCCUACUAGUCAGAGUGGAUAACCUCGUAAUUCACGAGGCUUCAAGUAGAGUAUUAAAAGGAAUUUUGUCUCAUUAGCAGGUUAAAAUCAGCUCUAGACUAGAUGUUCUGGUCCCUCCUGUCAAUAUUAUUACAAUAUAUUUGACAACCUUUAUGAAAUGGACAAAUUUGUUAAAAGACACAAAGUACUAAAUCAUACUCAAGAAGAAAUAGAAAAAGUCUGUUUAGAUUAUUAAAGAAAUUGAAUUUGUAGUUAAAACCCUUGCUACAAAGAAACUUCAAAGGCUGAAUUGCUUCAGUGUUUAAUUCUUUUCUGUUUGUUUGUUUGUUUGUUUUGAGACAAGGUCUCACUCUCUCACCCAGGCUAUAAUACAAUGGCACAAUCAUGUCUCACUGCAAGCUCAAACUCCUGGGUUCAAAUGAUCCUCCUACCUCAACCUCCCGAGAAGCUAGGACGACAGGUGCAAACCACCACAGCUGGCUAAUUUUUAAUUUUUGUAGAGAGGAGGUCUCGUUUUGUUGCCCAGGCUGGUUUCAACCUCCUGCACUGAAGCGAGUCCUUCUACCUCAGCCUCCCAAAGUGCUGGGAUUACAAGCAUGAGCCACUGCACUUGGCAGUGUUGAAUUUUAACACAGAUUUCAGAAAGAUGUAGUACCAAUUGUAUACAAACUGUCCCAGAAAAUUGAAGAGGGAGAAAUAUACCUAUCUUAUUUCAUGAGGUCAGCAUUACCUUCAUACCAAAAACAAAGUAUUGCAAGAAAACUACAGACCAAUAUCCCUCAUAAACACAGAUGUAAAAAUUCUUCAAAUAAUUUUAGCACAUCAAACCGAACAAUAUAUUAAAAGAGUAAUUCAUCAUGACUAGGAGUGUAGAAUUGGUUUAGCAUUUUGAAAUCCAUCAAUGUAAUUAAAUAUGUUAAGACUAAAAAGAAAAAUCACAUGAUUAUCCUAAAAGCUUUUGAAAAAUCCAGACAUCUAUUUCUGUUAAAAGCCCUCGGAGGCUGGGCAUGGUGGCUCAUGCCUGCAAUCCCAAUAGGGAUUGGUGAGGGUCAGGAGUUUGAGACCAGCCUGGCCAACAUUGCAAAACCUCAUCUCUACUAAUAAUACACAAAAUAGCAGGGCAUGUUGGUGGGCACCUGUAAUUCCAGCUACUUGGGAGGCUGAGGCAGGAGAAUCGCUUGAACUGGGGAGGCAGAGGUUGCAGUGAGCCAAGAUCAUGCCACCACACGCCAGCCUGGGCAACAGGGUGAAACUGUGUCAAAAAAAAAAAAAAAACCCUUGGAAUAGUAGAAGCAUGAAAAAAUCCAGAUUUAGAAAGAAGGAAGUAAAACUGUCUCUAUUAUCAAAAGCAUGAUCAUCUUCAUACAAAAUCUGAUGUCAUCUUCAAAAAGCUAUUAGAACUGGCUGGGCAUAGUGCAUCACGCCUGUAAUCCCAGCACUUUGGGAGGCCGAGGCUGGUGGAUCAUUUGAGGUCAAGAGUUCUAGACCAGUGUGGCCAACAUGGCAAAACCGCGUCUCUACUAAAAAUACAAAAAUUAGCUGGGCAUGGUGGCACACGCCUGUAAUUCCAGCUACUUGGGAGGCUGAGGCAGGAGAACCCGGGAGGCUGACCUGAGGCAGGAGAACCCAGGAGGCGGAGGUUGCGAUGAGCCGAGAUCAUGCCACUGCACUCCAGUCUGGGCGACAGAGCAAGACUCUGUCUCAAAAAAAAAAAAAAAAAAAAAGCUAUUAGAACUAAGUGACGUAGCAAGAUUGUAGCAUACAGAAUAAAAAAUUUAAAUCUCAAAUGUAUUUUUCUAUAUUAGCAAGAAACAACCAGAAAUUUAAAAAUACGAUUUCCAAUACCAUCAAAAAGUAUAACAAAGUAUUUACUUUGGGAUAAACCAGACCAAAGAUGUAUACACUGAACACUACAAAACAUUGUUGAAAAAAUUUAAGAAGACCCAAAUGGGAGAUAUAUCAUGUUCAUAGAUUAGAAGACUCUGUAUUGUUAAAUAUAAAUUCUACUCAAAAUAAUCUAUAGUUUAGUGUAAUUCAGUCAGAAUUUCAGAAGUUUUUUUUAAAGUCAAGUUGAUUCUAAUAUUUAUAUGGAAAAGCACUGGACUAGAGUAGCCAAACCAACGUGGAUUUUAAAAACCAAAUCAGAAGACCUUUACAUGAUUUGAAGACUUAUUACAAAGCUACAGUAAUCCAGACAAUGUGGCAUUGGUGUAAUGAUAGACAAAUAGUCAAUGGAACAGAAGGGAACGUCCAGAAAUAGACCUAAAUUUAUUUUUCAACAAUGUUUCAGAGGCUUUUUCAUGGAGGAAGAAAACAGUCUUUUUGACAAGUCGUUCUGGAGCAAUUAAAUAUCCAUAUCUAAAAACGCAAACUUCAACCCACGUAACAAACAACUGCACGGCUAUUAGAAUGUCUGAAAGUGUGACCAUACCAAAUAUUGGUAAGGAUAUAUGGAGCAGCUAGAAUGUAAAAUGGUACAACUACUUUGGAGAAUGGUGUUCUUGUUUCUUACAAAGUUAAAUAUACAUCCUCCAAAUGACCUAGCUAUCCCACUCCUAGAUAUUCACCCAGGACAGAUGAAAGCAUCUGUCCAUGUAAAGACAUACACAGGUGUUUAUAGCAGCUUUAUUUGUAAUGGCCAAAGUCUGGAAAACAAACCAAACAUCCACAACUAGUAACUGGUUAAACAAAUUGUGAUAUUUCCAUAGAAUAGAAUACUACUCAACUAUAAAAGAAUUGUACUAUUGAUAAGAAAUGAACCAACAGCAUAGAAGAAUUUUAGAAUACCUAUGCUGAGUGUAAGAUACUGUAAAGUACAUUCUAUAUGAUUCUAUUUAUAUUCUAGAAAGUGCUAACAAAUUUAUGGUGAUGGCAGAUCCAUUGUUGUCUGGGGACAGGGUUAUGCUAUGAGGCAGUGAUCACAAACGGGCAUGAGGAAACUUUUAGGAGUAAUAGAUGUGUUCCCAUUGAGGUUGUGGUUGCAGUACUUUAUACAUACGUCAAGUUUUAUCUAAUUAAACACUUUUAGUUUGUGCAGAUAAUUGUAUGUCAGUUAUACCUCAGUAAAGCUAUUAAAAUGAAUAUAUACUUUGAUUCCAUUUAUAUGUUUAAAAGUAGGAAACAUUAUUCUAAAGCCAUUAAGUUCCAAAAAUACACUGCUAAAAUGAAGAAGUGCCAAUUUGUUAUUUUUUGAUCACCAUAUAUGAAACUUCUGUUAUUUCCAUGGAAGAUCCCCUUAUAUUUAAGUAGCAAUGUCAAGCCAGAGGAAGAGUGUUUUGAUAGUCCUGGGUUCUAAUCAUGACAACUAAAAAUUAUCAUAACCUACCAUUGAAUAAUGCUUUAAAGUUAAAAAGGGUAUUCACAAAAACCGUCAUUUAAUCUACAAGGCAAUUCCAUGUGUUUUUCUAAUGCAUGUAAAGUUUCAGCUUGGCUCAUGGAAUAUAUUCUCAAUUUUUGUUAGGUAAUGUUGGUAGUAGUUUUAGGAGUAUUGAUCAUGUUAUCUAUUAAGUUUCACUUCACUUUAACUUGCUUUGAUAACUCACACUCUUCAUUCAUUCCUGUUAAAACAUAAUGAAUAUAGUACCAAGUGCAUGAGGGAAAACUCACAGCUAUUGGGCUGCUCUCUGCUAUACCACCUUACUUCUGUUCCAACAAAGUUAUUUGCUUACAAAAGUUAAUUAUGUUUUUCCUAAACUUGGUGAAAUUUGUGUUCAUUAUUUAAUUAUUUAACAUUAUAUAUUCUGAUGAAAUAUGAAUGCAAGUAGAAUGAGAAUUAGUUUAAUGAGUUAAGGUUGGUUCCAAAACUAAAUACAUAUGAGUUAUUUUUAAUGUUGCUAUUGAAUUGGAUGUGGGCAUGAAAAGUAUAAAAGAUUAAAGGCAGUAAAAAGCUGUAAACAUCUGUAUUCAGGAGUGCUUCAUAGGUGUUUUUAUGUUUUCUCUCUGCUUUAAAGAAGUUGAAACUAGGCCAGGAACCAUAGCGCACACCUGUAAUCCUAGCACUUUGGGAGGUUGAAGUGGGAGGAUUGCUUGAGCAGAGGUGUUGGAAACCAGCCUGGGCAACAUAGUUGGACCCCAUCUCUCCAAUUAUUUUCUUAAAAUUAGCCAGGCAUGGUGGCACACACUUGUAUUCCCAGCUAUUCGGGAGGCUAAGGUGGGAGGAUCGCUUGCACCUGGGAGGUUGAGGCUGCAGUGAGCUACGAUCAUGCAACUGCACUCCGGUCUGGGUAACAGAGUAAGACCCUGUCUAAAAAUAAAAUUUUUAAGAAAGUAAAAUGAGAAUUCAUAAACUAUGAAUUCUAGAUGUGGUUCUACAAGAAAAACUCUAGAAUGUCAGUCUGUAGGCAUGCUCAAAGGUUUUGACCCUAUUUUUUUUUUUUUUUUUUUGAGACAGAGUCUUGCUCUUAUUGCCUAGGCUGGAGUGCAGUGGCACCAUCACAGCUCACUGCAACCUCCACUUCCCAGGUUCAAGCAAUUCUCGUGUCUCAGCUUCCCGAGUAGCUGAGACUACAGGCGUGCACAACCAUGCCUGGCUAAUUUUUGUAUUUUUAGUAGAGAUGGGGUUUUGCCAUGUUGGCCAGGCUGAUUUUGAACUCCUGGCCUCAAGUGAUUUUGAACUGCCCACCUCUGCCUCCCAAAGUGCUGAGAUUACAGGUGUGAGCCCCCCACCCAGCUGACCCUAUUUUAAAUAUUAGCAAAUGAUGUAUCUUUAUAUAUUAAAAUAAAAUGUUUAGAUUAUGAAAGCUAUUUUUUGUUCCCUUAAUUUAAUCAUCACUCUGAUUUAUUUAUCAACUACUAUUCCUUUUCCUCAUCUGUAAAUUGAGGGGAUUUGCAUAGAAAUACUAGAUAAUCUUUUAAAUUUUUUCUUAAAGCUUAAACAUGUUAUAAAACUGAUGAUUCAUUUUUUUUCCACAUUCUAAGAUUAAUACUGUUAGAUUUUAUUAUAAAUUAAUAAAGUUCCUCUUUUAACAUGUAAAA